AUUCUAGGCUCCCCUGUGACAGCCGCGGCAGGAAGCAGGCGGGCGCUCCCCGGCCACAGGCCUGUUGUUCUCGGAAGGGAGAAAGCUGGACAUUUCCCCACGUAACUCCCAGCUCUGGGCCUAGAGUGCGUGCAUGGCGAAGUCCCCGGAGAACUCUACCCUGGAGGAGAUUCUGGGGCAGUAUCAACGGAGUCUCCGGGAACAUGCCAGCAGAAGCAUUCACCAACUGACAUGUGCCCUGAAAGAAGGCGAUGUCACUAUUGGAGAAGAUGCACCAAAUCUUUCUUUUAGCACCAGUGUGGGAAAUGAGGACGCCAGGACAGCCUGGCCCGAAUUACAACAGAGCCAUGCUGUUAAUCAGCUCAAAGAUUUGUUGCGCCAACAAGCAGAUAAGGAAAGUGAAGUAUCUCCGUCAAGAAGAAGAAAAAUGUCCCCCUUGAGGUCAUUAGAACAUGAGGAAACCAAUAUGCCUACUAUGCACGACCUUGUUCAUACUAUUAAUGACCAGUCUCAAUAUAUUCAUCAUUUAGAGGCAGAAGUUAAGUUCUGCAAGGAGGAACUCUCUGGAAUGAAAAAUAAAAUACAAGUAGUUGUGCUUGAAAACGAAGGGCUCCAGCAACAGCUAAAAUCUCAAAGACAAGAGGAGACACUGAGGGAACAAACACUUCUGGAUGCAUCCGGAAACAUGCACAAUUCUUGGAUUACAACAGGUGAAGAUUCUGGGGUGGGCGAAACCUCCAAAAGACCAUUUUCCCAUGACAAUGCAGAUUUUGGCAAAGCUGCAUCUGCUGGUGAGCAGCUAGAACUGAACUUUUUGAUCAUCUCAAACAAAAAGUCUGGACGUAUUAAACAAUAUCUCCAUUCCCCUCCCUGCCAACCCCUGAUGACCUCUCUUCAACUUUCGGAGAAGCUAAAACUUACUUAUGAGGAAAAGUGUGAAAUUGAGGAAUCCCAAUUGAAGUUUUUGAGAAAUAAGAAUCACGGCCGGGCGCGGUGGCUCACGCCUGUAAUCCCAGCACUUUGGGAGGCUGAAGCGGGCGAAUCACGAGGUCAAGAGAUUGAGACCAUCCUGGCCAACAUGGUGAAACCCCGUUUCUACUAAAAAUACAAAAAUUAGCUGGGCCUGGUAGCACGUGCCUGUAGUCCCAGCUACUUGGGAGGCUGAGGCAGGAGAAUCACUUGAACCUGGGAGGCGGAGGUUGCAGUAAGCUGAGACCACGCCACUGCACUCCAACCUGGCAACAGAUCUCAUCAUAUUCAACGUGUCAAUUAGAAUCACCACACCAAAGUUUCAGGGUCGUGGUAAAAAUUAAUAAGGUAUUGGACGUAAACUAAAGCAUAAGGAACGACUUAGCUGAAUAUCAGAGAACUUGUGAAGAUCUUAAAGAGCAACUAAAGCAUAAAGAAUUUCUUCUGGCUGCUAAUACUUGUAACCGUGUUGGUGGUCUUUGUUUGAAAUGUGCUCAGCAUGAAGCUGUUCUUUCCCAAACCCAUACUAAUGUUCAUAUGCAGACCAUCGAAAGACUGGUUAAAGAAAGAGAUGACUUGAUGUCUGCACUAGUUUCCGUAAGGAGCAGCUUGGCAGAUACGCAGCAAAGAGAAGCAAGUGCUUAUGAACAGGUGAAACAAGUUUUGCAAAUAUCUGAGGAAGCCAAUUUUGAAAAAACCAAGGCUUUAAUCCAGUGUGACCAGUUGAGGAAGGAGCUGGAGAGGCAGGCGGAGCGACUUGAAAAAGAACUUGCAUCUCAGCAAGAGAAAAGGGCCAUUGAGAAAGACAUGAUGAAAAAGGAAAUAACGAAAGAAAGGGAGUACAUGGGAUCAAAGAUGUUGAUCUUGUCUCAGAAUAUUGCCCAACUGGAGGCCCAGGUGGAAAAGGUUACAAAGGAAAAGAUUUCAGCUAUUAAUCAACUGGAGGAAAUUCAAAGCCAGCUGGCUUCUCGGGAAAUGGAUGUCACAAAGGUGUGUGGAGAAAUGCGCUAUCAGCUGAAUAAAACCAACAUGGAGAAGGAUGAGGCAGAAAAGGAGCACAGAGAGUUCAGAGCAAAAACUAACAGGGAUCUUGAAAUUAAAGAUCAGGAAAUAGAGAAAUUGAGAAUAGAACUGGAUGAAAGCAAACAACACUUGGAACAGGAGCAGCAGAAGGCAGCCCUGGCCAGAGAGGAGUGCCUGAGACUAACAGAACUGCUGGGCGAAUCUGAGCACCAACUGCACCUCACCAGACAGGAAAAAGAUAGCAUUCAGCAGAGCUUUAGCAAGGAAGCAAAGGCCCAAGCCCUUCAGGCCCAGCAAAGAGAGCAGGAGCUGACACAGAAGAUACAGCAAAUGGAGGCCCAGCAUGACAAAACUGAAAAUGAACAGUAUUUGUUGCUGACCUCCCAGAAUACAUUUUUGACAAAGUUAAAGGAAGAAUGCUGUACAUUAGCCAAGAAACUGGAACAAAUCUCUCAAAAAACCAGAUCUGAAAUAGCUCAACUCAGUCAAGAAAAAAGGUAUACAUAUGAUAAAUUGGGAAAGUUACAGAGAAGAAAUGAAGAAUUGGAGGAACAGUGUGUCCAGCAUGGGAGAGUACAUGAGACGAUGAAGCAAAGGCUAAGGCAGCUGGAUAAGCACAGCCAGGCCACAGCCCAGCAGCUGGUGCAGCUCCUCAGCAAGCAGAACCAGCUUCUCCUGGAGAGGCAGAGCCUGUCGGAAGAGGUGGACCGGCUGCGGACCCAGUUACCCAGCAUGCCACAAUCUGAUUGCUGACCUGGAUGGAACAGAGUGAAAUAAAUGAUUUACAAAGAGAUAUUUACAUUCAUCUGGUUUAGACUUAAUAUGCCACAACGCACCACGACCUUCCCAGGGUGACACCGCCUCAGCCUGCAGUGGGGCUGGUCCUCAUCAACGCGGGCGCUGUCCCCGCACGCAGUCGGGCUGGAGCUGGAGUCUGACUCUAGCUGAGCAGAGCUCCUGGUGUAUGUUUUCAGAAAUGGCUUGAAGUUAUGUGUUUAAAUCUGCUCAUUCGUAUGCUAGGUUAUACAUAUGAUUUUCAAUAAAUGAACUUUUUAAAGA